AUGUAUAUUUAGAGAUUGAUUUCUUAAUCUUGUUUAUAUAAUUUAAUUUGUUUUAUUUGUAAAUGAUUGGUCUCAUCUCAGGUGUUCUAGCAGAAGAGAUAGAUAAAUGGAUAGCUAACAAUGCAAUGUGAUAAGUACUAUAUUGGUAGUAUGAAUGAUGUGAUGUGAAAGCCUAGAGGAAAGAAUUAUUAAGUUUUGCCUUGGGAGAGGUGGAGUCAGGGAAGACUUUAUAGAUGUGUCUUUUUUUAAACCUGGUCCUUGAAGGAUGAAUAGGAGUUCAUUAAGGUUUUCUCUGCAUGAGUAACGAACAAUGUGAGAAUCAAGAUGUGGCAGUGUGAAUAUAUAGAGAUAGAAGGAAUGGUUCAUAGUCUGAUGUGGCUGGGUUGUAAGAUGGGAAAAGAAGGGACAGGAAAUGAAAUUGGGAAGGUAUGUGUACUUCAGAUUGUCACAGGCUUUGAAUACUGUGUUAAGAGUUAGAAUCUUAUUUUUAUUUAUUUAUUUUUUAUUUUGAGAUGGGAUCUCACCCAGACUAGUCUCAGACUCCUGGUCCGAAGUGAACCUCCCACCUCAGCCUCCCAAGUAGCUGGGACUACAGUCGUGUGCCACUGUGCUUGGAUCACGAAUUUUGUUUUAUAAACAAUGGCUAUUGGAAUUUUUUAGGGAUGUGAAUAAAUAUUCAAGGCACAUCUUACAUCAUUCCCUUAAGCCACUAAAAUAGCGGUCAAGCUAAUCUGUGUCUCUGAUUAUUUCUACUUCAAUCCAUCUUUCAUAUUAUUGUUAUUGUUGCUUUCUUAAAGAGACCUAACUGAGGCACUUCACUGGUCAAAAACCUUUACUUCUAGGAUGAAAUUCAAACUUCUAAAUGUGGCAGAAAUAGCACUUCACAAUUUGGCACUGUUCUUUCCGGCCUUAUCUUUAUAGUUAUUUUUUUCUUAAAUCUAAUAUUCUAGUCAUAUUAAGUGACUAGCCAUUUCUUGAACUUAGAUAUAGAUAUUGCUAUGAACCUUUGUUCCUGUAGUUCCUUAUAACUAAGAAACCAUUCUUACCCAACCCUCUCACUUCUCCUUUCUUCAUCUUGUGAACUCCUAUUUAUUCUUUAAGAGCAAAUGCUGCUUGUUCUGUAAAGGCUUAGCUGACUCUUUACCCAUGCAGAAUUAGUCACUUCUUAAUCUGUAUUCUCAUAAAACUUGACACAUAACUUCUAACACCCAUCAGAUUAUCUUAGAAUAAACUGUAUCUAUCUCCUUUGCCAGACUGUAAACCAUAUAGGGCAGGUGAAUAAACUGUAUCUAUCUCCUUUGCCAGAUUGUAAACCAUAUAGGGAAGGUUCUAUGUUUUACUAAUUCCUAUGGAUUAAUUUAUUGCCUAGCCUAUAGUAAAUGCUCACUAAUUGUAAACGAGUGAUCUAUGUUUUAGGAAGACAAUUCUCUUGAUAGCAUGGAGGAUUUUAAUGUAAUAAGGCCUCCAUUUACCUUUUGGUAUAGCUCUGCUAAUUUGUUUACUUGCCUGGGAUAGUCAGCUAGUCAGAAAGCAUUCAUUGAAUGUUUAUGAUUAUGCUGUUUGCUAGGCACUGAGGUUACUCUGGUGUAGAGGAGUGUCUGUUUCUAUACUCUUGGAGUGUGAGGUCAGGAUAAUAAGAUAAUUCCUUUUAGUAUUCUUAAAUGAUAUAGUACCUACUGCCUUUGCUCAUCUUGUAUUUUCUAUGAUCUGGGAUGCUCCAGCAGACAGAAGAGAAAGCAGACGACAGUUUAAAAGCAUAUAGCUUUUCAAUACCAAACAAGAGACAUGGUAGGGUUUUUGGGCAGGAGCAUAAUACCUUUGUUCAAAAAUGAGCAGUGGCGGCUGGGUGCAGUGGCUCACGCCUGUAAUCCCAGCACUUUGGGAGGCUGAGGCGGGCAGAUCACCUGAGGUCAGGAGUUUGAGACCAGCCUGGCCAACAUGGCGAAACCCUGCCUCUGCUAAAAAUACAAAAAAAAAUUAGCCAGGCGUGGUGGCGGGCACCUGUAAUCCCCACUACUCGGGAGGCUGAGUCAGGAGAAUCUCUUGAACCUGGGAGGUGGAGGUUGCUGUGAGCCGAGAUCAUGCCACUGCACUCCAGCCUAGGCAAUAAGAGUAAAACUCCGUCUCAGAAAGUCCACUCUUGGUAUUGGGAAAGAGAGAUUCAAGCAUUCUGUCAGAUUUUAAGAGCCACCAUGAUUGCUCUGGGCUUGAGUACAUGAAGCCAACUGCUUUAGUGACAGGUUGGCUGAAAUUUAACUUGUGCAUGAUUAAUUAAAAUUUAAAUUAGGGCUUUGGAGACUGUGGGUUUGAGAGCAUAUGACAGUGAAUAAUGAUGACCUGCAUAACAUCAGGUUAGUUGAAUGUGAGUUUUAGAAUGAAAAUCUUUUUGUAUGAAAACAUUCCUUAUAAAUAAUGUAACUUUUCUGAGCUGAAUUAAAAUAUACCCGGGGGGGUCAACAGUAUUUGAAUAAUCUUUUUUUUUUUGUAGACAACGACCAUUUUUCUUAUAUAAGAAAUACUUACCCAAUAAAUACUUAAUUUAGAAAUAACUUGUUCUUGGAAUGACUAACCCUCAUAUUGCUCUAUGUAAUACCAUCCCUUUGUUUCUAUUGUUAGAACUGUCUUAUGGGCCAGGCGUGGUAGCUUACACCUGUAAUUCCAGCAUUUUUGGAGGGCGAGGCAGGUGGGUCACCUGAGGUUGGGAGUUUGAGAGCAGCCUGAACAACGUGGAAAAACCUUGUCUCUACUAAAAAUACAAAAUUAGCCGGGUGUGGUGGCGCAUGCCUGUAAUCCCAGCUACUCGGGAGGCUGAGGCAGGAGAAUUGCUUGAACCCAGGAGGUGUGGAGGUAGCGGUGAGCCGAGAUCAUGCCAUUGCACUCCAGCCUGGGCAACAAGAGCGAAACUCUGUCUCAAAAAAAAAAAAAAAGUCUUGUCAUUGUGAGAAUCUGCAGUUUUAAGGGCCACUGAGGGUAGGGGAAGAAAUGUCAGAUAUUUUUGAAAAGUUUUGGCCUUGAAGGUAAAGUAAGGAAAGCUAUGAAAAUCAGGAACUGCUUAGGUGAUGUAACCUUGAGAGUUGGCUCCCAAGCAUAUAUGGUCAAUCUGUGUAUUGGUCCCUGGCCUAAUUCCCCCAUACCCCUUUCCCAUCACUACCUGAAAAUGUUCACAAUCCUUUUCCCCAACUCAUAUGUUGACCAGCUGGGUCUUAUUUGGAUUAAUAGGCUUCUUUUUUUUUCCCCUUAAUGCUAGUAUUAUUCUAUGAUAUCAACGACAGUGAGAGGUUGAGCAUCCCAAAUCCACAAAGCUCCGAAAUCCAAAACUUUUUGAGCACUGAAUGAUGUUCAAAGGAGAUGAUUGGAGCAUUUUGGAUUUUGGGUUUUCAGAUUUGGGAUGCUCAACCAGUAUGCAAAUAUUCCAAAAUCUGAAAAAAAAUUCCAAAAUCUAAAACACUUCUGGUCCCAGGCAUUUUAGAUGAGGGAUACUCAACUUGUACAGUAGAGGAUUUGGGGACAGCAUGAGAGACAGCACAAAGGACAGGAAGGGAGUACAAGAAAGUGUGAAGGUACCAGAAGACAAACUUGUCUGGAGUUGUCUUGUUACAGGAAAGGAAGAGGAGGUGAUAGGUCUCAUCCAUAUUGCCCUUUGAUUUCUGGAUUCAAAACACAGUAAUAGUAGUAAUGGUAGUACCAUGGUUCAACCCUAUUAUACAUACCCCAAAUUCAUUCAUUUAAGAAAUAUAGAUUGAGAAUCUAUAUUUGUGCAAGGUAGUGUACUAGGUACUGAGGCUAUAUCUGUAAACAGAAAUUCUUACUUUUUUGAUGUUUAGAUUCUGAGUAAAUUAUAUGUUAGAAAACAAUUAAUGAGAUGGGGAAAAAUACAGAGCAAGAUAAGAUCAGGAGUGGUAGGUUGCAAUUUUAACUGGAAUAGUGAGAAUACUCAUUGAAAAGUUGAGAUUUAAGCAAAGACAUGAAGGAUAUGAGGAUGUAAACUGUAUAGAUGUCUGAGGAAGAGCCUCUAGGCCAAGGGAACAGUCAAUGCAAUGGCUCUAAGGUGUGAGCAUGCCUGAUGUGUUGAAGAACAGUAAGGAGGUCAGUGUGGAUGUAUCAGAGUGAUUGAGUAGAACAGUAGGAGAUGAGGUCAGAGAUGUGGGGGAUGAGAUCACAGAGCCAGUGCAAGGUUUUUGAUUUUGAUACUGAGUGAAGUCAGUGGAGGGUUUUGAGUAGGGUAGUGAUGUGAUCUAACUUAGCUUUACAUUUUGUUUCUCUCUCAUUUUAUUGUGAACAUUUUCAAAUGUAGAAAAGAGUGAAUAGUAUAAUGAAUACUUAUAACCCCAUUACUUACAAUUAAGUUUAUUAACAUGUUGCCAUAUUAAAAAUAUUAAUUUAUGUUACAAAUAUCAUGAAAGCUUCUUCCUAAAUACUAUAGUUUACGGUUUUUAAAAGGAAGGGCAUUUUCCUUUUUUUUCUUUUUUUGAAUGGAGUUUCACUCCUGUUGCCCAGGCUGGAGCGCAUGGCGCAAUCUCGGCUCAUCGCAACCUCUGCCUCCUGGGUUUAAGCGAUUCUCCUGCCUCAGCCUCCUGAGUAGCUGGGAUUACAGGUGGCUGCCACCACGCCUGUCUAAUUUUGUAUUUUUAGUAGAGGUGGGGUUUCUCCAUGUUGGUCAGGCUGGUCCCGAAUUCCCGACCUCAGGUGAUCCUCCAGGAUCAAUUUCAUAACAUAAUUAGAUUACUGUCAUAUAAUAAACCUAGACUGUAUUCAUAUUUUCCAAAUUGUCCCCAAAAUGCAUUUUACACCUGGUAUGUUCACAUGAUGAUCUAAUCAAAGACCACAUGUUGUAUUUGAUUGUCAAGAUUCUUCGUCUCUUUUAAUUUAGAAUAGUUCCCCACCUUCUCCAUUUUUUAAUGGCGUUGACUUAUUGAUGAGACCAUUCCUAGAAGACCUCAUCUUUUGGAUUUAUCUAAUUGCUUUUUCAUCUUAUUUGUUCUUUAUUUCCUGUAUUUGUUCUAUACUUGGAGUUAGGUCUAAAGGCAAAAUAUUUAAUGGCAAAAAUACUUCAUAGAUUAUGUAACAUCUAAUGUUCGACUGUCUUUAAAUGGUUCAGUAAGUUUGUGAUAGUCUGAUUCCUCAGUUAUACAAUGGCAUCCCCCCACCCCCCCACCACCUUUCCCUUCAAUAACAAAUUAUCUGCAGGUUGAUACUUUGGCAGCCUGGGAAUAUCCAGUUUCUCAUCAACUUUACAUUAAAUGGUUUAGAAUCCAUGGAUGACCUUUGCUUGAGCCACCUUUCCCUUUAGGGGUUCCAAAUUGAUGAUUUACUAAUUUUAUCAUGCCCUAUAUAUUUAUUAGCUGUCAUUCUUCUAAUAAAGAAGAGUUGUCCCUUACUAACUCAGGCUGUUUGCUUUCCUUGAAAUACGGUUCCUACUGGAAAGGCAGGACAAAUGAUUAAUAUUUUCCCACUAAUUACGAGCUAUCAGAGUAAGGAGUUUCUUUAAUAGCAGCCUCCAAUGGUGACGUGAGUUGGGUGUGUACAUGUGUGUCUGUGGUGAGAGAGAGAGAGAGAGAGAGAAUGCAUGUGUGUGUGUGGUUACUUAGAUUUUCAAUGGAUCAGUCUGAUUGUGUGUGGCAGCAGUGGAUAUUGAUGAGAUUCUGAAUGUAUUUGAAGGUAAACCAAUAGUGUUUGCUGAUGGAUUGGAUACAGGAUGUGAGAAAGUAGAGUUAAGGACUAUUCUGAAGUUUUUUGGACUGAGCAGUUAAAAAGAUAGUGUUGUCACCAACUUAGGGAAAAUUUCAGGUAGAUUGGGUUUGGAGUGUUGGGAGGGAGAAUUAGGAAUUCACUUUGCGCAUGUUAAGUUUGAGAUGUCUCUUAGACAUCCAAGUGUAGAUAAUCGACAUAUGGAUCUGAAGGGGUGGGUUGCCCCUCCGCACCUGUGGGUGUUUUUCGUUAGGUGGAACGAGAGACUUGGAAAAGGAAGAGACACAGAGACAAAGUAUAGAGAAAGAAAAAAAGGGGGCCCAGGGGACCGGCGUUCAGCAUACGGAGGAUCCAUGCCGGCCUCUGAGUUCCCUUAGUAUUUAUUGAUCAUUAUUGGGUGUUUCUCGGAGAGGGGGAUGUGGCGGGAUCAUAGGAUAAUAGUGGAGAGAAGGUCAGCAGGUAAACACGUGAACAAAGGUCUCUGCAUCAUAAACAAGGUAAAGAAUUAAGUAUUGUGCUUUGGAUAUGUAUACACAUAAACAUCUCAAUGCCUUAAAGAGCAGUAUUGCCACCCGCAUGUCCCACCUCCAGCCCUAAGGCGGUUUUCCCCUAUCUCAGUAGAUGGAAUAUAUGAUCGGGUUUUACACCGAGACAUUCCAUUGCCCAGGGAGGAGCAGGAGACAGAUGCCUUCCUCUUGUCUCAACUGCAACGAGGCGUUCCUUCCUCUUUUACUAAUGCUCUUCAGCACAGACCCUUUACGGGUGUCGGACUGGGGGACGGUCAGGUCUUUCCCUUCCCACGAGGCCAUAUCUCAGGCUAUCACGUGGAGAGAAACCUUGGACAAUACCUGGCUUUCCUAGGCAGGGGUCCCUGCAGCCUUCCGCAGUGUUUUGUGUGCAGUGGUUUGUGUCCCUGGGUACUUGAGAUUAGGGAGUGGUGAUGACUCUUAACAAGCAUGCUGCCUUCAAGCAUUUGUUUAACAAAGCACACCUUGCACAGCCCUUAAUCCAUUUAACCCUGAGUUGACACAGCACAUGUUUCAGGGAGCACAGGGUUGGGGGUAGGGUUACAGAUUAACAGCAUCUCAAGGCAGAAGAAUUUUUCUUAGUACAGAACAAAAUGGAGCCUCCUAUGUCUACUUCUUUCUACACAGACGCAGUAACAAUCUGAUCUCUCUUUCUUUUCCCCACAUGGAUCUGAGUAAAUAAUUGGAUAUACGGACCUGGUGUUCAAGAGAAUAGACCAGGCCAGAAAUAGAAGUGUGGGCAUCAAAAGCAUGUAGAUGCUAUAUAAAUACAUGACAUUGGAUGAAAUCACUAAGGGUUGUAUACAGAGAGGCAAGAGAAGAGAACCAAGGACUAAGGCUUGGGGCACUCCAGUGUUAAGGGUCUAGGAGAAGACGAGGAACCAGCAAAUAAGGUAGAUGAGGAACAACAUGUAAAGUAGGAGGAAAAGAGAGAAUGUGGCAUUUUGGAAGCUAAAUAGAGGAAGGAAUGAUUAACCAUCAAAUGCCUCUGAUAGGUCAUUUAAGGACUGAAAAUUAACCAUUGGAGGGAGGUCAAAACUAGCAGUUUUGGUGGAAUUGGGUGAUAUUAAGAGAUAAUGGAAAGAGUAGAAUUGGAGACAGUGACAAUUGACAACUUUAUCAAGCAGUUGCUACAAAGGGGUGCAGACCAAAUGGGAUGGUAGAUGGCAAGGGAAGUGGGUUCGAGAUUUUUUUAAGAUGGGAGAGAGAACGCAUUUGUAUUCUGAUGGGUAUGACUGAGUGGAAAGUGGAGAGCUGGUGUUACAGGGGAGAGAGGUGAGAAUUAUUUGGAGCGGUGUUCUUGAGGAUAGAGAAAAUGGAGUUUGGUGCUUAAAUGGGUGGAUUAACUUGAUAUAGGAGGAUAGAGAGUUUAUCAUAACAGGUAUAAAGGCAAUAUAUGUAGAUAUAGUUGGGUAGGUGUGAUUGGGAGUUUGUAGAAGUCUAAUUGAUCUAAUUUUCUUACUGAAGUAGAAAGCAAGGACAUCAGCUGAGAGGAUGAGAGAGGGAGGUAUUGGAGGUUAGGAGAGAAGGUAGGGAAGUACAGUUAUGUGCUGCACAAUGAUGUUUCGGUCAACAAUGGACCACAUAUAUGACGGUGGUUGCAUAAGAUUAUAAUGAAACAGGAACACGUAGCUGAAGAAGAGGCCCAAGAAAAGGAAACUACAGGAGAAGAACCCCCAAGAAAAUUCACAGUAAAGGGUUUAGCAGAAGCUUUUCAGCAAGCUCCUUAAAAAGUUUGAAAACGUGGGCCAGGCACGGUAGCUCACGCCUGUAAUACCAGCACUUUGGGAAGCCGAGGUGGGUGGAUCACUUGAGGUCAGGAGUUCGAGACCAGCCUGGCCAACAUGGAGAAACCCUGUCUCUACCCAAAAACGGAAAAAUUAGCUGGGCUUGGUGGUGCAGACCUGUAAUCCUGGCUACUAGGGUGGCUGAGGCAGGAGAAUCACUUGAACGCGAGAGGUGGAGAUUGCAGUGAGCCGAGAUCGUGCCACUGCACUGCAGCCUGGGUGACAGAGCAAGACUCCAUCUCAAAAAAAAAAAAAAAAGUUUGAAAACAUGGACCCCAAUGCUGACCAAGGUUUUUAUUAAUAGAGAGGAAUGUACAUGGCGCAUUGUCUGCUUACAAGCGAAUCUGUGAUGAAACAAACAAACCAGGCAAACCAUCGUGGCAUGGACAUAUUUCUGAAAAGAGUGACACCUCCUCAAGAAGAGCCUCAGGUCCUUCAGGAGGAACCAAAUGGCGAGACACCAUCAUCUUUAUACAGAGUUGCAGCAGUACUUCUACAAUUUAAUCUUAUUGAUUUAGAUGAUCUUUAUGUACAUCUUCUUCCGGCUGAUAAUUGCAUUAUGGAUGAACACAAACGAGAAAUUGCGGAAGCUAAGCAAAUUGUUAGAAAGCUUACGAUGGUUGUGUUGUCUUCUGAAAAAAUGGAUGAGCGAGAGAAAGAAAAGGAAAAAGAAGAGGAGAAAGUAGAGAAACCACCUGAUAACCAAAAACUUGGCUUGUUGGAAGCCUUAUUAAAGAUUGGUGAUUGGCAACAUGCACAGAACAUUAUGGAUCAGAUGCCUCCAUACUAUGCAGCUUCACACAAGCUAAUAGCCCUUGCUAUUUGCAAGCUCAUUCAUAUAACUAUUGAGCCUCUCUACCGAAGAGUUGGAGUUCCUAAAGGUGCUAAAGGCUCACCUGUUAAUGCUUUGCAAAACAAGAGAGCACCAAAACAAGCUGAGAGCUUUGAAGAUUUGAGGAGAGACGUGUUCAAUAUGUUCUGUUACCUUGGUCCUCACCUUUCUCACGAUCCCAUUUUAUUUGCAAAAGUGGUGCGCAUAGGCAAGUCAUUUAUGAAGGAGUUUCAGUCUGAUGGAAGCAAACAAGAAGAUAAAGAAAAAACGGAAGUUAUCCUUAGCUGUUUGCUUAGCAUUACUGACCAGGUACUACUUCCAUCUCUUUCUUUGAUGGACUGCAAUGCUUGUAUGUCUGAGGAACUAUGGGGAAUGUUUAAAACAUUUCCAUAUCAGCAUAGAUAUCGUCUGUAUGGCCAGUGGAAGAAUGAAACUUAUAACAGUCACCCACUUUUAGUAAAAGUUAAAGCUCAAACAAUAGACAGAGCCAAAUAUAUCAUGAAGCGCCUAACCAAGGAAAAUGUGAAGCCUUCUGGAAGACAAAUUGGGAAGUUGAGCCACAGCAAUCCAACCAUUUUGUUUGAUUAUGUAUGUUUUGAGAUCUUGUCACAAAUACAGAAGUAUGAUAACUUAAUAACACCUGUAGUAGAUUCAUUGAAAUACCUCACUUCACUGAAUUAUGAUGUCUUGGCCUAUUGUAUCAUUGAAGCUUUAGCUAAUCCAGAAAAGGAAAGAAUGAAACAUGAUGACACAACCAUCUCAAGCUGGCUUCAGAGUCUGGCUAGUUUCUGUGGUGCAGUUUUUCGUAAAUAUCCAAUUGAUCUUGCUGGUCUUCUUCAGUAUGUUGCCAAUCAGCUAAAGGCGGGCAAAAGUUUUGACCUGCUUAUAUUGAAAGAAGUGGUACAAAAAAUGGCAGGAAUAGAAAUUACAGAGGAAAUGACAAUGGAGCAACUAGAGGCUAUGACUGGUGGAGAGCAGCUAAAAGCUGAGGGUGGUUAUUUUGGUCAGAUCAGAAACACUAAAAAAUCCUCUCAGAGAUUAAAGGAUGCUCUAUUGGACCAUGAUCUUGCCCUUCCUCUCUGUCUGCUUAUGGCUCAGCAGAGAAAUGGGGUAAUCUUUCAGGAAGGUGGAGAGAAACAUUUGAAACUUGUGGGAAAGCUCUAUGACCAGUGUCAUGAUACCCUGGUGCAGUUUGGUGGGUUUUUAGCAUCUAAUCUGAGCACAGAAGAUUAUAUAAAGCGAGUGCCUUCAAUUGAUGUACUCUGUAAUGAAUUUCAUACACCCCAUGAUGCAGCAUUUUUCCUGUCUAGGCCAAUGUAUGCCCAUCAUAUUUCGUCAAAGUAUGAUGAACUUAAAAAAUCAGAAAAGGGAAGUAAACAGCAACAUAAAGUUCAUAAGUACAUUACAUCAUGUGAGAUGGUGAUGGCGCCUGUCCAUGAAGCAGUGGUCUCCUUACAUGUUUCCAAAGUCUGGGAUGACAUCAGCCCUCAAUUCUAUGCUACAUUCUGGUCAUUGACAAUGUAUGACCUUGCAGUUCCACACACCAGCUAUGAACGAGAAGUCAAUAAACUUAAAGUCCAGAUGAAAGCAAUUGAUGACAAUCAGGAAAUGCCCCCAAAUAAAAAGAAAAAAGAGAAGGAGCGCUGUACUGCCCUUCAGGACAAGCUUCUUGAAGAAGAAAAGAAACAGAUGGAACAUGUACAGAGAGUUCUACAGAGAUUGAAACUGGAAAAGGACAACUGGCUUUUAGCAAAAUCUACCAAAAAUGAGACCAUCACAAAAUUUCUACAGCUGUGUAUAUUUCCUCGAUGUAUUUUUUCAGCAAUUGAUGCUGUUUACUGUGCUCGUUUUGUUGAAUUGGUACAUCAACAGAAAACUCCAAAUUUUUCCACACUUCUUUGCUAUGAUCGAGUUUUCUCUGACAUAAUUUACACAGUUGCAAGCUGUACUGAAAAUGAAGCCAGUCGAUACGGAAGGUUUCUUUGCUGCAUGUUAGAGACUGUGACCAGGUGGCAUAGUGAUAGAGCCACAUAUGAAAAGGAAUGUGGAAACUAUCCAGGAUUCCUUACCAUAUUACGGGCAACUGGAUUUGAUGGUGGAAAUAAGGCUGAUCAAUUAGACUAUGAAAAUUUUCGACAUGUUGUACAUAAAUGGCAUUACAAACUAACCAAGGCAUCGGUACAUUGCCUUGAAACAGGCGAAUAUACUCACAUCAGGAAUAUCUUGAUUGUGCUAACAAAAAUACUUCCUUGGUACCCAAAAGUUUUGAAUCUGGGUCAAGCUUUGGAAAGAAGAGUACACAAAAUCUGCCAAGAAGAAAAAGAGAAGAGGCCAGAUCUAUAUGCAUUGGCUAUGGGUGUUGAAGUUUAUCUUCUGCCUUCAGGAGAUUAUGGGAGAUUAUGCGAUCAUGUUUCCACAGGCUGCUACUCUGGGCAGUUGAAAAGUAGAAAGUCAUACAUGAUACCUGAAAAUGAGUUUCAUCACAAAGACCCCCCUCCGAGGAAUGCAGUUGCCAGUGUGCAAAAUGGGCCUGGUGGUGGGCCUUCUUCAUCAUCAAUAGGAAGUGCAUCUAAAUCGGAUGAAAGCAGUACUGAGGAGACUGAUAAAUCAAGGGAGAGAUCUCAGUGUGGUGUGAAAGCUGUUAAUAAAGCUUCUAGUACCACACCUAAAGGGAAUUCAAGCAAUGGAAAUAGUGGCUCUAACAGCAACAAAGCUGUUAAAGAAAAUGACAAAGAAAAAGGGAAAGAGAAAGAAAAAGAGAAAAAAGAAAAGACUCCAGCUACUACUCCAGAGGCCAGGGUACUUGGUAAAGAUGGUAAAGAAAAACCAAAGGAAGAGCGGCCAAAUAAAGAUGAAAAAGCAAGAGAGACCAAGGAAAGAACGCCGAAGUCUGACAAAGAGAAAGAAAAAUUCAAGAAGGAAGAAAAAGCUAAAGAUGAGAAAUUUAAGACCACUGUCCCCAACGCAGAAUCAAAAUCAACUCAAGAAAGGGAAAGAGAGAAGGAGCCAUCCAGAGAAAGAGAUAUAGCAAAGGAAAUGAAAUCAAAGGAAAAUGUUAAAGGAGGAGAAAAAACACCAGUUUCUGGGUCCUUGAAAUCACCUGUUCCCAGAUCAGAUAUUCCAGAGCCUGAAAGGGAACAAAAACGCCGCAAAAUUGAUACUCACCCUUCUCCAUCACAUUCCUCCACAGUAAAGGUUACAGCCAUACUUCCCAAAGUUCCUCUGGGUUCUGAGAACUAUGCCAGCUCACCUGUCAUCUCCAUUCAUUUUCUACAGGACAGUCUCAUCGAACUCAAGGAAUCUUCAGCAAAGCUCUACAUUAAUCAUACUCCUCCACCACUGUCCAAGAGUAAGGAGAGAGAAAUGGACAAGAAAGAUUUGGACAAGUCAAGGGAAAGAUCCAGAGAAAGAGAGAAAAAAGAUGAAAAGGACAGGAAAGAGCGGAAAAGGGAUCACUCAAACAACGACCGUGAAGUGCCACCGGACUUAACCAAGAGACGUAAAGAGGAGAAUGGAACAAUGGGGGUUUCAAAACAUAAAAGUGAAAGUCCUUGUGAAUCUCCUUAUCCAAAUGAGAAAGACAAGGAAAAAAAUAAGUCAAAAUCUUCAGGCAAAGAAAAAGGCAGUGAUUCAUUUAAAUCUGAGAAGAUGGAUAAAAUCUCCUCCGGUGGCAAAAAGGAGUCCAGGCAUGAUAAAGAAAAGAUAGAAAAGAAAGAGAAACGGGACAGUUCAGGAGGAAAGGAAGAGAAGAAACAUCAUAAGUCCUCGGACAAGCACAGAUAAUGAAGACUUUCCAUCAAGGUGAGAUCGGACUGGAACUGUUCGGCUGCGACCAGAAAUUUAUUUUCCUGAGUAAAUUGCCGAGAAUUAAGAAUGAAGAGGGCCAUUUGCAUCUCCUUAAAUUAUUCAGUUACCUGCUUUAUUGCUCCAUGUGGAAAACUUAAAAUUGUUAAGUUGUGCAUUACUGUAUUUUAACUUGUUGCUUAGUUUCUACAUGUUUAUUUUCAGUAAUGGCUGAAAGUGUUAACUGUUCCAUACUUUUAGCACAAUGUGCUGCAUAAGGUUACCUGUGUACAGAGUUUUACUUUAGAUUAACUAAAUAUUGCCUGGGUUCAGUUUUUAUUUCCAUUCUGAAAUGCUUCCUUUUUAUUGUUUGAAACUGAAAAUAAACAAUUGUUGAACCCUUUUGAUUUUACCUCAUUUUAAAACUGUUUUAAUUUAUUAUUUGGCUUGUUCUUAAUAUUAGUCACUAAAAGCAGUGGGAGCAUUGUCUUAUGAAAUGCUUAGGAAUCAUUUUAUAUAGUACAUGUACAACAUUAAACGUGUUUAAAAAAGAAAAAGGUACCAGCGAUCACUUGUCCCUUGCCAUUUUUUCUUGUAAUUAUGUUAGACAAAUCUUGGCGGCGGGGGGAUCAAAACAUAAUUGUUUUAAUUCUACAGCUGUAGGAGCUUUGUAUUGCUGAACUUUCAUCUGGAAAAGUUUCACAGUGACAUUUUUAAAAGAGAAUUUUUUUAUCUGCCGAAUUCUACCAGUGUAACCUUUUUUCUAAAUAAACAAUAGUUUUCUCAAA